AGGGCAGCCCCAGCUCAGACUCCCCAGCGCCAGCCUUUACACCGCUUCCUCCUCGGAAAAAGAAGAAUUUUUUCUUGAACUGGAACUGCAACUAAAGUCCGUUCGGAGAUCCAAAAAUCUGCAAUACAGAGGUUAUUUGUAACCCGGCGUCUCCAGGCUGGUGAGCAAGCUGAGGAGAGCAAGAGGGAUGGGGAGCGGCGCCGGGGAGCUGGGCCGGGCUGAGAGGCUGCCAGUGCUCUUUCUCUUCCUGCUGUCUUUGUUCUGCCCGGCGCUCUGUGAGCAGAUCCGCUACAGGAUUCCCGAGGAAAUGCCCAAGGGCUCCGUAGUGGGGAACCUCGCCACGGACCUGGGGUUCAGCGUCCAGGAGUUACCGACUCGAAAACUGCGCGUCAGUUCGGAGAAGCCUUACUUCACCGUGAGCGCAGAGAGCGGGGAGUUGCUUGUGAGCAGCAGGCUAGACAGGGAGGAGAUAUGCGGGAAGAAGCCAGCUUGUGCUCUGGAAUUUGAGGCUGUUGCUGAAAAUCCACUGAACUUUUAUCACGUGAAUGUGGAGAUCGAGGACAUUAAUGACCACACGCCAAAAUUCACGCAAAAUUCCUUUGAGCUGCAAAUAAGUGAGUCUGCACAGCCUGGCACACGAUUUAUAUUAGGAUCUGCCCAUGAUGCGGAUAUUGGUAGCAACACACUGCAGAAUUACCAACUCAGUCCCAGUGAUCAUUUCUCACUGAUAAAUAAAGAGAAAUCAGAUGGCAGUAAAUACCCUGAGAUGGUAUUGAAGACACCUUUGGACAGAGAAAAGCAGAAAUCCUACCACUUGACUUUGACUGCCUUGGACUUUGGAGCUCCACCCCUAAGCAGCACUGCACAGAUACACGUUCUAGUGACUGAUGCCAAUGAUAAUGCUCCAGUGUUCAGUCAAGACGUAUACAGGGUGAGCCUUUCAGAAAACGUGUACCCGGGGACCACGGUGCUACAGGUGACUGCCACGGACCAGGAUGAGGGUGUCAAUGCCGAGAUUACUUUCUCUUUCAGUGAAGCUAGCCAGAUCACCCAAUUUGACCUGAACUCUAACACCGGGGAAAUUACUGUUUUAAAUACAUUAGAUUUUGAAGAAGUCAAAGAAUAUUCCAUAGUUUUGGAAGCAAGGGACGGUGGAGGAAUGAUUGCGCAAUGCACAGUGGAGGUAGAAGUCAUAGAUGAAAAUGACAACGCCCCAGAAGUGAUAUUCCAGUCUCUACCCAACCUAAUUAUGGAGGACGCCGAGCUGGGAACACAUAUUGCUUUGCUCAAAGUCCGUGACAAGGAUUCCAGACACAAUGGAGAAGUGACUUGUAAAUUGGAAGGUGAUGUUCCAUUUAAAAUAUUAACUUCUUCAAGAAACACGUAUAAAUUAGUGACAGAUGCUGUUCUAGACCGCGAGCAGAAUCCAGAGUACAAUAUAACCGUUACGGCAACAGAUCGGGGCAAGCCUCCCCUCUCCUCCAGUUCCAGCAUCACCCUGCACAUUGGUGAUGUAAAUGACAACGCUCCGGUUUUCUCACAGUCUUCCUAUAUAGUCCACGUGGCCGAGAACAACCCGCCUGGAGCCUCUAUUUCACAAGUCAGGGCUUCUGAUCCGGACUUGGGGCCCAACGGCCAAGUCUCUUACUGCAUCAUGGCCAGUGACCUGGAGCAGCGGGAGCUGUCAUCCUACGUGUCCAUAAGCGCGGAGAGCGGGGUGGUGUUCGCGCAGCGCGCCUUCGACCACGAGCAGCUGCGCGCCUUCGAACUCACACUGCAGGCCCGCGACCAGGGCUCGCCAGCGCUCAGCGCGAACGUGAGCCUGCGCGUGUUAGUGGACGACCGCAACGACAAUGCGCCACGGGUGCUGUACCCCGCGCUGGGUCCCGACGGCUCUGCGCUCUUCGAUAUGGUGCCGCACGCUGCAGAGCCUGGCUACUUGGUGACCAAGGUAGUGGCGGUGGACGCAGACUCAGGACACAACGCCUGGCUGUCCUACCACGUGCUGCAGGCUAGCGAGCCCGGGCUCUUCAGCCUGGGGCUGCGCACGGGCGAAGUGCGCACAGCGCGUGCCUUAGGCGACAGGGACGCCGUCCGCCAGCGCCUUCUGGUCGCCGUGCGUGACGGUGGACAGCCACCACUCUCGGCCACUGCCACGUUGCACCUGGUCUUCGCCGACAGCUUGCAGGAGGUGCUGCCGGAUAUCACUGACCGCCCCGACCCCUCUGACCUCCAGGCUGAGCUGCAGUUUUACCUAGUGGUGGCCUUGGCCUUGAUCUCAGUGCUCUUCCUCGUGGCCAUGAUUCUGGCCAUUGCCUUGCGCCUGCGACGCUCCUCCAGCCCCGCCUCCUGGAGCUGCUUCCAGCCUGGUCUCUGUGUUAAAUCCGAAUCCGUGGUUCCCCCCAACUACAGCGAGGGGACUUUGCCUUAUUCCUACAAUCUAUGUGUUGCACAUACAGGAAAGACGGAGUUUAAUUUCCUAAAAUGUAGUGAGCAGUUGAGUUCAGGACAAGACAUACUUUGCGGUGAUUCAUCUGGGGCCUUAUUUCCACUUUGUAAUUCCAGUGAAUUGACUUCCCAUCAGCAAGCCCCGCCCAACACGGACUGGCGUUUCUCUCAGGCCCAGAGACCCGGCACCAGCGGCUCCCAAAAUGGCGAUGACACCGGCACCUGGCCCAACAACCAGUUUGACACAGAGAUGCUGCAAGCCAUGAUCUUGGCGUCCGCCAGUGAAGCUGCUGAUGGGAGCUCCACCCUGGGAGGGGGUGCCGGCACCAUGGGAUUGAGCGCCCGCUACGGACCCCAGUUCACCCUGCAGCACGUGCCCGACUACCGCCAGAAUGUCUACAUCCCAGGCAGCAAUGCCACACUGACCAACGCAGCUGGCAAGCGGGAUGGCAAGGCCCCAGCAGGUGGCAAUGGCAACAAGAAGAAGUCGGGCAAGAAGGAGAAGAAGUAACAUGGAGGCCAGGCCAAGAGCCACAGGGCGGCCUCUCCCCAACCAGCCCAGCUUCUCCUUACCUGCACCCAGGCCUCAGAGUUUCAGGGCUAACCCCCAGAAUACUGGUAGGGGCCAAGGCCAUGCUCCCCUUGGGAAACAGAAACAAGUGCCCAGUCAGCACCUACCCCUUCCCCCCCAGGGGGUUGAAUAUGCAAAAGCAGUUCCGCUGGGAACCCCCAUCCAAUCAACUGCUGUACCCAUGGGGGUAGUGGGGUUACUGUAGACACCAAGAACCAUUUGCCACACCCCGUUUAGUUACAGCUGAACUCCUCCAUCUUCCAAAUCAAUCAGGCCCAUCCAUCCCAUGCCUCCCUCCUCCCCACCCCACUCCAACAGUUCCUCUUUCCCGAGUAAGGUGGUUGGGGUGUUGAAGUACCAAGUAACCUACAAGCCUCCUAGUUCUGAAAAGUUGGAAGGGCAUCAUGACCUCUUGGCCUCUCCUUUGAUUCUCAAUCUUCCCCCAAAGCAUGGUUUGGUGCCAGCCCCUUCACCUCCUUCCAGAGCCCAAGAUCAAUGCUCAAGUUUUGGAGGACAUGAUCACCAUCCCCAUGGUACUGAUGCUUGCUGGAUUUAGGGAGGGCAUUUUGCUACCAAGCCUCUUCCCAACGCCCUGGGGACCAGUCUUCUGUUUUGUUUUUCAUUGUUUGACGUUUCCACUGCAUGCCUUGACUUCCCCCACCUCCUCCUCAAACAAGAGACUCCACUGCAUGUUCCAAGACAGUAUGGGGUGGUAAGAUAAGGAAGGGAAGUGUGUGGAUGUGGAUGGUGGGGGCAUGGACAAAGCUUGACACAUCAAGUUAUCAAGGCCUUGGAGGAGGCUCUGUAUGUCCUCAGGGGACUGACAACAUCCUCCAGAUUCCAGCCAUAAACCAAUAACUAGGCUGGACCCUUCCCACUACAUAAUAGGGCUCAGCCCAGGCAGCCAGCUUUGGGCUGAGCUAACAGGACCAAUGGAUUAAACUGGCAUUUCAGUCCAAGGAAGCUCGAAGCAGGUUUAGGACCAGGUCCCCUUGAGAGGUCAGAGGGGCCUCUGUGGGUGCUGGGUACUCCAGAGGUGCCACUGGUGGAAGGGUCAGCGGAGCCCCAGCAGGAAGGGUGGGCCAGCCAGGCCAUUCUUAGUCCCUGGGUUGGGGAGGCAGGGAGCUAGGGCAGGGACCAAAUGAACAGAAAGUCUCAGCCCAGGAUGGGGCUUCUUCAACAGGGCCCCUGCCCUCCUGAAGCCUCAGUCCUUCACCUUGCCAGGUGCCGUUUCUCUUCCGUGAAGGCCACUGCCCAGGUCCCCAGUGCGCCCCCUAGUGGCCAUAGCCUGGUUAAAGUUCCCCAGUGCCUCCUUGUGCAUAGACCUUCUUCUCCCACCCCCUUCUGCCCCUGGGUCCCCGGCCAUCCAGCGGGGCUGCCAGAGAACCCCAGACCUGCCCUUACAGUAGUGUAGCGCCCCCUCCCUCUUUCGGCUGGUGUAGAAUAGCCAGUAGUGUAGUGCGGUGUGCUUUUACGUGAUGGCGGGUGGGCAGCGGGCGGCGGGCUCCGCGCAGCCGUCUGUCCUUGAUCUGCCCGCGGCGGCCCGUGUUGUGUUUUGUGCUGUGUCCACGCGCUAAGGCGACCCCCUCCCCCGUACUGACUUCUCCUAUAAGCGCUUCUCUUCGCAUAGUCACGUAGCUCCCACCCCACCCUCUUCCUGUGUCUCACGCAAGUUUUAUACUCUAAUAUUUAUAUGGCUUUUUUUCUUCGACAAAAAAAUAAUAAAACGUUUCUUCUGAAAA